AGAGUGCGGGGUGGCAGCGGCGGGUCAGAGGGGUGCUUUGGGCGUAGGGUGGGGCGCGGGCAAUGGAGCAGAGUAUGGGAGAACGCGCUCGGAGUAAAGCACACGGCGCGGCGAAGGCGUGGCGGGAGUGUGCGGCGCCGGACCCGGGAAGCUGGCCUGGGCGCCGGGUCUCGAGUGCAGGCCUUUGUUCUGAAGUGUCCAGGCCGGCCUUGCGGCGUCGGGACUGAGGAAUGGAGCCCGUCGCGGGGCGGGGCGGGAAAGGAAGGUUCAAGUCUCUCGGGUUGAUGCGCAAGUUUCCGUCCCCAUCGGCCGGACAGAUUAGAAUCCUUUCAGGUGCUAGGUGAAUACAGAUGGGGCGGUGCUGCUUGCUGAGUUAGCCUUUGCGCGGGCACAGGCCUGGCUUUUUUGAGGCAUUGCACAGAAGGCUCAGAACAGGGCCAGGGAGCGGGGUGGUGUAUCCGGAUCCGUAGUCUGGAAAAGCUCCCUCUGGCUGCCGUGUGGGGAACAGAAGGGGAGGCGAGGGGCGCAGAGACACCAGCCAGGUUUCUUCAUCCGUCCAGGACAGCGGGAACGGGGCAGUGGAGAUGGCGGCUGCAGAGGCUGUGCAUCACAUACACCUGCAGAACUUCUCACGCUCUCUGCUUGAGACCCUCAAUGGGCAGAGGCUUGGGGGACACUUCUGUGACGUGACUGUGCGCAUUCGUGAAGCUUCGCUGCGUGCCCACCGCUGCGUGCUGGCGGCCGGCUCACCCUUCUUCCAAGACAAGCUGCUGCUCGGCCACUCUGAGAUCCGUGUGCCUCCGGUGGUGCCCGCGCAGACAGUGCGACAGCUGGUAGAGUUCCUGUACAGCGGUUCGCUCGUUGUGGCGCAGGGUGAAGCCCUGCAGGUGCUCACGGCCGCGUCAGUGCUUCGCAUACAGACAGUUAUCGACGAAUGCACGCAGAUUAUCGCCCGCGCUCGAGCCCCGGGCACCUCUGCGCCCACGCCCCUGCCCACCCCUGUGCCCCCGCCACUCGCACCUGCGCAGCUGCGUCACCGCCUGCGCCACCUGCUGGCUGCACGUCCCCCGGGGCACCCCGGUGCUGCACACAGCCGUAAGCAGCGCCAGCCCGCGCGUUUGCAGCUGCCAGCGCCCCCAACACCUGCCAAGGCUGAGGGGCCUGAUGCUGACCCCUCACUGUCCGCGGCCCCUGAUGACCGAGGUGACGAGGAUGACGAGGAAAGUGACGAUGAGACCGAUGGCGAGGAUGGCGAAGGUGGCGGCCCAGGCGAGGGCCAGGCACCUCCUUCCUUCCCAGACUGUGCUGCUGGCUUCCUCACUGCUGCUGCUGACAGCGCGUGCGAGGAGCCCCCUGCACCCACUGGCCUCGCUGACUACAGUGGUGCCGGGAGAGAUUUUCUUCGGGGAGCUGGGUCAGCUGAGGACGUAUUUCCAGACAGCUAUGUAUCCACUUGGCACGACGAGGAUGGCGCUGUCCCCGAAGGCUGUCCCACUGAGACCCCUGUCCAGCCCGACUGCAUACUGUCUGGAUCCCGCCCGCCUGGUGUGAAGACCCCAGGGCCGCCCGUUGCACUCUUCCCCUUUCACUUGGGUGCCCCUGGGCCACCCGCACCACCCCCUUCAGCACCAUCGGGGCCAGCCCCUGCGCCCCCACCCGCCUUCUACCCCACACUCCAGCCCGAGGCAGCCCCCAGUACUCAGCUGGGGGAGGUCCCGGCUCCCUCUGCUGCUCCCACCACGGCCCCCUCAGGCACCCCUGCUCGCACCCCAGGUGCUGAGCCACCUACGUAUGAGUGCAGCCACUGUCGCAAGACGUUCAGCUCCCGGAAAAACUACACCAAGCACAUGUUCAUCCACUCGGGGGAGAAGCCGCACCAGUGCGCCGUGUGCUGGCGAUCCUUCUCUCUACGCGACUACCUGCUCAAACACAUGGUCACGCACACCGGCGUGCGCGCCUUCCAGUGCGCCGUCUGCGCCAAGCGCUUCACGCAGAAGAGCUCGCUCAACGUGCACAUGCGCACUCACCGGCCCGAGCGCGCGCCCUGCCCCGCCUGCGGCAAGGUCUUCUCGCACCGCGCGCUGCUGGAGCGCCACCUGGCGGCGCACCCUGCGCCCUGAUGGCGCUGGGGCCUGGCCUCGCCCACGGUGGAUCCGGGGCCUCCCGCACAGUCGGCCACGCCCGCUGCGGGACCCGUGGUUCCCGCCACUAGACCACGCUCCCUCCUGAGCGCAGGUCCUCUCUCUCCCUUCACCCUUUCUCCAUACCAGGGCCUAAGUCCGCCUUACUCCUCUCCUCCAUGUACUUGAACCCUCCAGGUGGUGCCGGGCUGGGGCUGGGGCUGGUUAGACCACUUCUGAGAACUGGACUAUUUCCUGCGUAAACCGGGCGCUCAGGCGCUUGGACCCGGCCCAAGAUUUGACUCCGGUUCUCACCCCGCCCUCUCCUGGGGUGGUGGUGGGGGCUGGGGGGCCGCUUGCCUGCCCCAGGGUCAGGCUGGGCAAGGUCCCUAGCUCUCUACCCAAGCUGUUACUCCCUCAUGGGGCGCCUAAGGAGACUCAAGUGGACCCAUCAUAUAUGGGGGCUGGGCCUCGGGACUCUCGCUCUAAUAAAGGACUGUAGGCCAUGGGGCCUAAACCACGAA